GCAAUGGCGCCAUCUCGGCUCACCGCACCCUCCGCCUCCUGGGUUCAGGCGAUUCUCCUGCCUCAGCCUCCCGAGUAGCUGGGACUACAGGCACCCGCCAUCAUGCCCGGCUAAUUUUUGUAUUUUUUGUAUAGGUGGGGUUGUAGAGAUGGCGUUGUAGAGAUGGCGUGAGCCACCGCGCCAGACCGGAUUGGUUAGAUACAACUUUCUUUUUUUUUUUUUUUCUUGAAGUGGAGUUUCGCUCUUGUCGCCCAGGCUGGUAUGCAAUGGCGCCAUCUCGGCUCACCGCAACCUCCGCCUCCUGGGUUCAAGCGAUUCUCCUGCCUCAGCCUCCCGAGUAGCUGGGAUUACAGGCACCCGCCAUCAUUCCCCACCAUCAUGCCGGGCUAAUUUUUGUAUUUUUUGUAUAGAUGGGGUUGUAGAGAUGGCUCAAGCCACCGCGCCCGGCCGGAUGCAUUAGUUUUCUUACCCCCAAAAAACCUUUUUUUUUUUUUUUUCCCCCGAGGCAGAGUUUCGCUCUUUUCGCCCAGGCUGGAGUGCAGUGGCGCCAUCUCGGCUCACCGCAACCUCUGCCUCCUGGGUUCAAGCGAUUCUCCUGCCUCAGCCUCCCGAGUAGCUGGGAUUACAGGCACCCGCCAUCAUGCCCCGCCACCAUGCCCGGCUAAUUUUUGUAUUUUUUGUAGAGAUGGGGUUGUGGAGAUGGCUCGAGCCACCGCGCCCAGCCGGAUGGGUUAGUUUUCUUACCCCAAAAAACAGAUACACCUUUUUUUUGGUUUGUUUUUUGUUUUUUUUUUUUUUUGAGGAGUUUCGCUCUUGUUGCCCAGGCUGGAGUGCAAUGGCGCCAUCUUGGCUCACCGCAACCUCCGGUUCCCGGGUUCAAGCGAUUCUCCUGCUUCAGCCUCCCAAGUAUCUGGGAUUACAGGCAUGAGCCACCGCGCCCGGCCCAACAGAUACAACUUUCUACCUCGUAAUAAUGUUUCAAGGAUUAUAUGAGGUAAUCUUUAGAUGGUGGAAGAUCUCUCUAAGGAGUGAGUAUCGAUCAACAAAACCUGGAGAAGCAAAAGAAACCCAUGAAGACUUCCUAGAGAAUUCACAUCUUCAAGGUCAAACUGCCUUAAUAUUUGGUGCAAGAAUAUUAGACUAUGUCAUCAAUUUGUGCAAAGGUAAAUUUGACUUCCUUGAACGGCUCUCAGACGAUUUGCUCCUGACUAUCAUUUCUUAUCUGGAUCUUGAAGAUAUUGCCAGGCUUUGUCAAACAUCACACAGAUUUGCAAAGCUGUGCAUGUCUGAUAAACUGUGGGAACAGAUAGUCCAGUCGACCUGCGACACCAUCACUCCUGACGUGAGGGCCCUGGCGGAGGACACAGGCUGGAGACAGCUGUUCUUCACCAACAAGCUCCAGCUCCAGCGGCAGCUCCGCAAGAGGAAACAAAAAUAUGGAAACCUGAGAGAAAAGCAACCUUAGGCACACAUUUUCCUACCAGCAGGGAGCUCAGGCAUGGCUGUGUUUCUCUUCAGUGUCCAAAUCUCUUCUGUCUCCUUUUCUUAAGAACUAAGAGGUUUUGUUGAUGCGUGGAGCCAUUUGAAACUCGUAGGGGAUUUGCACACAAAUGCAGCAGAGUCUGGCUCCCCAGUGCCUUGCUAGAGUCACCGUCAUUCUGAGGUCAAAUCAUGGCCCGAGGACAAGGGCUGUAAGACAGGGAGCCCCAUAGGCCAUCAUCAUCCUUAUCCCACACCCAUUAUAAAAGAGGUUUCUAUUGUAUAUAAACAAACAAUAAAUGAUUAUUAGCAGGUUUUUAUUAGACAUCUAUUUUAUCUAGGCAUUAGAAAGGGUAAUGGGGCUUUUGAAUUUUUUCCUGGCAUUGUGUCGUCUGCGUCCAGCCAUGAAGCUGGUGGCUGAGUGUCCCCACCAGGAACUGUGAAGGGCACGUACCACGGGAGGCACUCAGGGUGGGUGCAGCUGCCUUCCCAACUUUGUUCUGCUAAGUCCAUAUUCAGGGCCCUAUCCUUGUGAGCCCAGGAUGCCAGGGUCCAUCCCCGCAUGUAGACAGCUUCCGACCUGGUGCUGGAGCAUGACUGGAGAAGUGCAGGCAUCCUGCUUGCGGACCUUGCUCAAAGUACAACUUCCCAGGACUACUUCACAUUGUUAAAUAAACCUAUAAACAUUUCUUUUCUUUUCUUUUUUUUUUUUUUUUUGUAUUUUCUUUUUAGUAGAGGUGGAGUUUCGCCAUGUAGGCCAGGCUGGUCUUGAACUCCUGACCUCAAGUGAUCUACCUGCUCUGGCUUCCAAAGUGCUGGGAUUACAGGCAUGAGCCACUAUGUCUGGCUAAAACCUAUAAACAUUUCUUAGAGAAAUGCUGUUCCCCAAAGGAAUGUGAACAGCUACCACUUUUAACAAGGAUAUUUAAGAAAACAGACUAUGAGUUAACUAAGUAAAAAUGUAAAUAUGGUUUGCAUGCUGUUAACAUGGCAGAGGGGUAAAAAGAAUACAGUCCUGGGGAGAAAGGUCACUUCACUGAGAAGGCUUACUUAAAAAUGUUUUUCUCCCUGCACUUUCAUGAUUAUUAAGUACCCCUAGAAAAUGAACUCAUAGCAGCAAAUAAUCUAAUGACUCCUUUUAGGUUACAGAGCAAAGUAGCUUUCUACUUCCACAUCACAUUAUAAUAUAGCCUUAUAAUUUCUUCUUUCCUGCAACCUUCACUUUCCUACCUAGGAAAACUCACCUCCGGUGCCAGAGAAACUUCCCAGGAUGCACUAGGGCCCUGUGAACAAUACAGAAGUUGUGGACUCUGGCUCUUUGUCCCACCUAAGUCCUUCCAGAAGGGCUCUACAGCAUGGCUUAGUGACAUUAAAAAAAAAAACUGAACCCAUGUUAAUAUCAAACAAGAUUUUAAUCUUCAUUCACACACCCUUAAAACCCAGUCACGGGGCUCCCCGGUGCCAGUUUGAGACCGUCAACCUAGCCCUCUCUGCUUCUCAUUGCUGGAGGUACACACAGUCAAAAGUUUUCCGUGACUGUGAAAUCCAGUGCAAUCUGCUUCCCAGCAGAUGAGGAGCCUGACGUGGUUAUGUCUGGAUUUAGUCCAAGAACAGAGCAAAGCUUUAAUUGUCAAGAGACCCAGGCCUCAUUCUCCACUUAGGAGAGUUUGCUAGGGCAGGUACAGGUAAAGGUAACCAGCAGGCAGCUGAGAGCAAGAAGGCACGUGCUCUGCAGAGCUCUAGCUGCCUUGGCUCUCCCUGAGCUCCCAGACUUCACUCAUGGCCUAAUUUUCAAUGACAGAACGUAGGUUUUAUCGUGAGGAUGCAGACACAACCACAAUUACGUAUGUCAACAUAACUUCAUAAAUAUGUAACUGUAACUUAUUGGUAACAUCAGUGCAAGAUGAUUAAAGCUUCAUGUGUAGUAUUUUAUCAACAAACAGAUUCUGAAAGCUUAUGGACAUGCGCAAUAGUUGAUUCAGCUUCAAUCAAUAAGAACAUAAAUAUGGCAAUUUGAAAACACUAUGUAUAUACCUACUCACAUAUAUAUUAUACUUACGAUAUAUACUUAUAUGUAGUAUAUAAUAAUAUUACAUAUAAAAAUGUUAUAAAAAUAAAUGCUAAAGUAAAUAAAAAAAGAGCCAUUAAUAUGUUAACUAUUGUUAAAUAAUAGCUAAAAUAAUACAGAUUAUUAAAUUAUUUUAAUACUUACUUGCCAUAA